GGGUGACAGAGCGAGACUCCGUCUCAAAAAAAAAACAAACCAAAACUGUCUUUAUGUCCUACCUAGCAUUUACUAAGUAGAAGAUGUGCCCUUUUGAAGGGCAUGUCUAUUCCUAGAACUUUAACUACAAUGCUUUGCAGUAGAAAUAUAUGCUAUUGUAUUAAGGUGAAGUGACUUUAGAAUUAGUAACUCGGUGUUGACAGAUCAUGCUGAUCGAAGAUUAGCCUUGGAGUUUGGAAAGCUGGAGAGCAUGUAUAUUCCAGAUGACCAGGAAAGGAAAAGUCAGAAAAACAGUUUUUAAGUAGUACUGUUAUAACGACCUGUAAAACUUGAAACGAGAGAAAGCUGUCUUCUAAAAUGAAGAAUUACAUAUUUAAAACAUUAAUUUCCUCAAUGAUACUGCUACAUAUCUGAAAAGGGUGGUUACGUAGCAUUUGGGACAGACCCGUCUCAGUGGUUUGAGGCAACAGGUGUGGCUGAAGAAAAGGUAAGGCUGGGGAAAAACCAACAUUUCUGGUCUAAACUGAUACUGUCUUCUUACCUGAGGCAGUUUCCUAUGCCCUGGUUUUCUCUGUCUGAAAAAUGCAUGAUAACACAUACUCUUCAAAUUAGCUCAAAAUGCUUGGUAGUUACCUACUAUUCCCUGACAGGCCACAGGCAGAUAGUUCUAUGCUUGUUUUAGAAAUGGAGAAUUUGGUACUCAGAAAAGUUGAAGAAGCUUCAUUUCAUUCACAUAGUGAGUCAGCAACAAAGACAGACGGAAAAACAUGUCCUAUGACUCCUGCCAUUGUAUUCCUUCUCUUCUGCAUUGUGUUGCCUUUUGAUAUUUCACGAAGGUUUUGUGAUUGGUGAAAUAAAUUAAAGCACUUCCAUGAAGGAGACAAAAUGUAACCCAGUGUCUGCUGAUGGUGGUUAGUGACGAGGACAGGAGAACACUGCCUCAUAAUGGGGACUAUCCGGUGAGGGCUCCUUUUCACAGGUGCCCACACUGUGAGUCACCUCCUUAUGCUGAGAGUUCGGUAUGCUAUCAUAAAAUACUUUGUUGUGUAUUAUUUAUGAAGGACUAGAGUAUCUAUUGUCUCACUUUCUUUCAUUCUCAUGAGGUAGAUUACAGCAGCAGAUGGCAUUAUGCAUGCUUUAUCCCAGACACAAGAAAAUAAUAUCUGCCACUUACUGAGUACCUUGCUGGACCCAGACACUCUUACAUAUUUAUAUCUUCCCAUUGGGUCAUCCCGUGGACCUUGUGAAAUAUGUGGAAUAGCUCCAUUGUUAUAGAUAUGAACCCAGGGCUCAGAGAAGCUAAGUAAUUUGUUCAGGGUCACACAGACUUACAGGUCUGUCAGACUCCUAAGACCCUGAUGCUUUCAUUGUGCUGCAUUUCCUUCAAAUUAUGAACUUGCCCUAUGUCAGCACAGAAACGGCCUCUUCAGCCUAGCCCAGUGCUCCAACUGAUUGUUCUCUCUCAUAAAAGGCACUCACAACUAACCACUUGCUUGAUUUAGGAAUUCACUGAUUAGAUUGCUAGACCAGUUAAAGGCAAAUUUCAAUAAUGAGAGCAGUUAUCACGUAUCUAGUACUUACCAUGCGCCAGACUAUGAUCUAAAUUUAUGACACAUAUUAAAUCAUUUAAGCCUUACAACCAUGUAUAAAAUAGUGAACUGCGAUAUGAUGGAGUUGCUCUUAUCUUCAUCCCGGGAUGAGAAAAUAGAGGCAGAAGAGUUUUAAGCAAUUUGCACAGUUAAUAAAGUGUGGAGCCAGAAUUUGAACCCAAUCUGGCUCCAGACCUCUUUACUACAGCUCUCAGUUAGAAAAUUAUUUCUAACUGAGAUAUUUCGGUUCAGCAAGUGUUGGCUUAGUUCCUGUGUGCUAUGCCAGCAGAAAAUAUAGUUCCUACACAGAAGAGCUUACAUUUUUGACAUAAAUCAAAAUGUAUAUACUUGAAAUAAAUGCUACAACACCUUAGCAUAUGGGGUGUAAAUGUUGUGUAUGGAUCAGCAUGAAUAAUAGAGACUGUUAGUGAGUGGCUUGAGAGUUAAUUUGCCUUCGCAAGUAAUGUUCUUGACUAUGGACGAGUGACUUGGGCACUGGGGAGAAGCUGUUCCAUGUGUUCUAAAAUAAGCAGGUUACUUGGCUACUGUUCAAACUCUAAAUAGGUAUAUGGGUUGUAGCUAUUUGACCUGAACUAACUUUAAAUUCCCCUGAGUCCUUAUAUGAUUUUGGGGAAAAAAAAAAAAGGAAGAAGAAAAAAGAAAACUUUUCUCUGUAAAUGCUGCAUUUAAAUUAGAAUUUAUUAAAUUCUCUGCAAAAUACCGCCAGGCUGACAGGAAGGGGAUUCACAGUAAGCUCUUCCAGAAAGAAGGGGAUUUGGAUCCUAAUUGUCUCUUAUCUGGAGCACCCAACACAGUGCCUGAUCUUUAAAUGGAUGAGAUGGCUACCACUCAGAUUUCCAAAGAUGAGCUUGAUGAACUCAAAGAGGCCUUUGCAAAAGUUGAUCUCAACAGCAACGGAUUCAUUUGUGACUAUGAACUUCAUGAGCUCUUCAAGGAAGCUAAUAUGCCAUUACCAGGAUAUAAAGUGAGAGAAAUUAUUCAGAAACUCAUGCUGGAUGGUGACAGGAAUAAAGAUGGGAAAAUAAGUUUUGACGAAUUUGUUUAUAUUUUUCAAGAGGUAAAAAGUAGUGAUAUUGCCAAGACCUUCCGCAAAGCAAUCAACAGGAAAGAAGGUAUUUGUGCUCUGGGUGGAACUUCAGAGUUGUCCAGCGAAGGAACACAGCAUUCUUACUCAGAGGAAGAAAAAUAUGCUUUUGUUAACUGGAUAAACAAAGCUUUGGAAAAUGAUCCUGAUUGUAGACAUGUUAUACCAAUGAACCCUAACACCGAUGACCUGUUCAAAGCUGUUGGUGAUGGAAUUGUGCUUUGUAAAAUGAUUAACCUUUCAGUUCCUGAUACCAUUGAUGAAAGAGCAAUCAACAAGAAGAAACUUACACCCUUCAUCAUUCAGGAAAACUUGAACUUGGCACUGAACUCUGCUUCUGCCAUUGGGUGUCAUGUUGUGAACAUUGGUGCAGAAGAUUUGAGGGCUGGGAAACCUCAUCUGGUUUUGGGACUGCUUUGGCAGAUCAUUAAGAUCGGUUUGUUCGCUGACAUUGAAUUAAGCAGGAAUGAAGCCUUGGCUGCUUUACUCCGAGAUGGUGAGACUUUGGAGGAACUUAUGAAAUUGUCUCCAGAAGAGCUUCUGCUUAGAUGGGCAAACUUUCAUUUGGAAAACUCGGGCUGGCAAAAAAUUAACAACUUUAGUGCUGACAUCAAGGAUUCCAAAGCCUAUUUCCAUCUUCUCAAUCAAAUCGCACCAAAAGGACAAAAGGAAGGUGAACCACGGAUAGAUAUUAACAUGUCAGGUUUCAAUGAAACAGAUGAUUUGAAGAGAGCUGAGAGUAUGCUUCAACAAGCAGAUAAAUUAGGUUGCAGACAGUUUGUUACCCCUGCUGAUGUUGUCAGUGGAAACCCCAAACUCAACUUAGCUUUCGUGGCUAACCUGUUUAAUAAAUACCCAGCACUAACUAAGCCAGAGAACCAGGAUAUUGACUGGACUCUAUUAGAAGGAGAAACUCGUGAAGAAAGAACCUUCCGUAACUGGAUGAACUCUCUUGGUGUCAAUCCUCACGUAAACCAUCUCUAUGCUGACCUGCAAGAUGCCCUGGUAAUCUUACAGUUAUAUGAACGAAUUAAAGUUCCUGUUGACUGGAGUAAGGUUAAUAAACCUCCAUACCCGAAACUGGGAGCCAACAUGAAAAAGCUAGAAAACUGCAACUAUGCUGUUGAAUUAGGGAAGCAUCCUGCUAAAUUCUCCCUGGUUGGCAUUGGAGGGCAAGACCUGAAUGAUGGGAACCAAACCCUGACUUUAGCUUUAGUCUGGCAGCUGAUGAGAAGAUAUACCCUCAAUGUCCUGGAAGAUCUUGGAGAUGGUCAGAAAGCCAAUGACGACAUCAUUGUGAACUGGGUGAACAGAACGUUGAGUGAAGCUGGAAAAUCAACUUCCAUUCAGAGUUUUAAGGACAAGACGAUCAGCUCCAGUUUGGCAGUUGUGGAUUUAAUUGAUGCCAUCCAGCCAGGCUGUAUAAACUAUGACCUUGUGAAGAGUGGCAAUCUAACAGAAGAUGACAAGCACAAUAAUGCCAAGUAUGCAGUGUCAAUGGCUAGAAGAAUCGGAGCCAGAGUGUAUGCUCUCCCUGAAGACCUUGUGGAAGUAAAGCCCAAGAUGGUCAUGACUGUGUUUGCAUGUUUGAUGGGCAGGGGAAUGAAGAGAGUGUAAAAUAACCAAUCUGAAUAAAACAGCCAUGCUCCCAGGUGCAUGAUUCGCAGGUCAGCUAUUUCCAGGUGAAGUGCUUAUGGCUUAAGGAACUCUUGGCCAUUCAAAGGACUUUUCAUUUUGAUUAACAGGACUAGCUUAUCAUGAGAGCCCUCAGGGGAAAGGGUUUAAGAAAAACAACUCCUCUUUCCCAUAGUCAGAGUUGAAUUUGUCAGGCACGCCUGAAAUGUGCUCAUAGCCAAAACAUUUUACUCUCUCCUCCUAGAAUGCUGCCCUUGACAUUUCCCAUUGCUGUAUGUUAUUUCUUGCUCUGUUAUCUUUUGCCCUCUUAGAAUGUCCCUCUCUUGGGACUUGCUUAGAUGAUGGGAUAUGAAUAUUAUUAGACAGUAAUUUUGCUUUCCAUCCAGUAUGCUAGUUCUUAUUCGAGAACUAUGGUCAGAGCGUAUUUGGAUAUGAGUAUCCUUUGCUUAUCUUUGUAGUACUGAAAAUUUGCCGAAGUAACUGGCUGUGCAGAAUGUAAUAGAAGCUUUUCUUAUUCUUUUAUUCUUAAGAUCAGUAUCUUUUUACAGUAUUCUUUCUACAUGAUCCUUUUUUGUACAUUUAAGAAUAUUUUGAUUAUAUUAAACAAGACUGCUGAUUUUGCUACUUUUUUUAAGGGGUCUUCAAGUAAGUAAAACAUACAUCGUAGCUAGAAGAAAAAUGUACCUUAAAUUUGCAUCUUCCCUCUCAUACCCAAGCUGUAAACAAUUGAAAUAUUUUGUCUUAAAUCACUUGGUUCAAUACAUGCUUAUUUGUUUUAAAACCUGUAUCAUCAAACUCUCUCUCUAAAUUUAAAAUGCUGUUGAAUAUGAUACUUUUGAGGAGAGAGUGUGCUCAGAACUUAGACGGGAUUUGGUAGGCCAAGUAUGCUAAGUGUACAAUAUAUUUUUUAAUUUUACACCUGAAACAAAGAAAUGUGGUCACUAAAAAUAAAAGUAUAUAUGUAGGAAUUAAUGUACUCUUGCUUUGUCAAGCUGUUUGCUAUAGUUUCCAAGGUAUUAUGUUACUCUAACUCUGAAAAGUGAUGUAAUCUGGUAGCAAUGUAGUAGUUCAAAUAAAGGCAUUUACAUAAUAAUUAGUCUGUUCUUCAUGCUUUUGUCUCUUAGGAAGUAUGCCAAUGUUUGUCAGGAUUUUUUUCUUUUUGUUUUUCUGAUGUAUUCUGUAAAAUGGUGUUUGUUAAAUUUGAGUUUUGGGAGCUGAAUUAGAGGUACUGAAUUAAGGACAGUACAAAUGAAGUAAAAAGGUUUUCUCCAAUUUACCAAAA